GGUGCCUUAGGCGCUGGAGAAAAACUUCACCCGCGCCCACAGGCCCCCUUUCCGCAGGCUGCGCUGGCGGUUCAGGUUUGCAGGCCGGAAGUGAAAUGUUCUUUUUUGAUUUUUAAAAAGGAAGCCUCCGGCCCUAUGGUUUUCUGGGGUUGGAGUGGAUGUGUGUGCUGGGGGAGGCGGAGACGUCCCGCUCCAGGCAGGGCCUUGGGUCUUAAUAGGUGGGGAAAUCUCUGCCAAAUAGGAGGCCUCUCGGAGCCUCAGUUUCCCCAUCUGCAGACUGGGCUCUGACUUCUUCUGGCAUGAGAGGGUGUGUGAGAGUAAAAGGAGGCAGCUAGCCCCGUGCCGGGAGACACGAGGAACCCAGGUGCACUAAGGUCAGCCAUGUCAUCUGAGCCUCCCCCACCACCACAGCCCCCCACCCAUCAAGCUUCAGUCGGGCUGCUGGACACCCCUCGGAGCCGUGAGCGCUCACCAUCCCCUCUGCGGGGCAACGUGGUCCCAAGCCCACUGCCCACUCGCCGGACGAGGACCUUCUCGGCGACGGUGCGGGCUUCACAGGGCCCCGUCUACAAAGGAGUCUGCAAAUGCUUCUGCCGGUCCAAGGGCCAUGGCUUCAUUACUCCAGCUGAUGGCGGCCCCGACAUCUUCCUGCACAUCUCUGAUGUGGAAGGGGAGUAUGUCCCAGUGGAAGGCGACGAGGUCACCUAUAAAAUGUGCUCCAUCCCACCCAAGAAUGAGAAGCUGCAGGCCGUGGAGGUCGUCAUCACUCACCUGGCACCAGGCACCAAGCAUGAGACCUGGUCUGGACAUGUCAUCAGCUCCUAGGAGAUGGUGGAAGCACCCCUUGUCCUGUGCUUGUGGGAGACUUUGCAGGGAGGAGGCAGCAGACACUGGAGAUGACAUUCUUCCACACGAGACGGGGCUUCAGCCGGGCAUGGUCCCUCUCAAGUAUCUCCUGGAGGAAGGGGUAUGGGGGGCAGGUGUGGGGUGUGGGGUGUUCCCGGCCAUCAGCACAGCCUAUGACCAUUGCAACAACCUCUCACCAUCUGAAGAGCAUUAAAAGCAUUUAAAAAGGAGAGGUGCCCACUGGUGGCUGAGUGGAGGUUCCAACCCCAUCCCAGGGAGUGGAUCAAGGGUGGUAUUUCUCCAGCUGCUCAGACACAUGGGCUCAACCCACAGAAUCCCUCUUCCUCCUGGAGCUGGAGGCCCCAGAUUCCCAGAUCUGGCCCCCUGGCAGCCUGACAGGGACCUUGCGUGACUUCUCCAAGGCAAAUUUCCACCUAAGUGCCCCUUGCGCCUCUCCUGGGGCCUGGGCAAAGCAGUUUUCUAAUUCUUGGCUUGGUUGGUUCUAGGGGAGCUGGCUUGAAGUGGGUGGGGAAAGGCGGGGGUGGCGGUCUUUGGAUUGGACGGAUGUUGCCUUUUGGUGCCUUUGCAGUGGGAGGCGGCAUAGCUGCCUGUCUGGGGAAGACAGUUCUCCCAGCACUCCCACCCCUGGGCACAGCAGGCUGGUACUGGGAGGCUGAACCCCUCUUAGAGCCUGACCUUUUCAUCUGCCUUCUGGUUGUGUGACCAUCACUCAACAGCCAUUUCACAGCCCCUGUAAUUAUGGCGGCGGGGGGCUGGGGUGGUGGUGGUGGGAAGGGCUUGUGGAGAGGACACAGUCUUUGUUUAAAAACUUUGUCCCGAUCCAUCCAGAAAAGAGUAGGUAGCUUGCAUCCUGACAGCCUGGCAAAGUCAAGAAAGUUGAAGGAGAAACAUACCUUUGGAGAGGGGGUUUUCUUUAAAACUAGUGUUAAGAAAUGCUUAGGGAUUUUUUUUUUCUUAUUUUUCAUAACUAAAGCUUUCACCCAGAGCCGGCUCUGUUUGCACUUUGCUGCCGACAUUGCAAACUUUUUGGCAGGGUGGGAGACUGAGUCUCAUUCUGUCACCCAGGCUGGAGUGCAGUGGCCCGAUCUCAGCUUACUGCAACCUCUGCCCUCCAGGGUUCUGGCAAUUCCGCCUCAGUCUCCUGAGUAGCUGGGAUUACAGGCAUGCGCCACCACACCCGGUUAAUUUUUGUAUUUUUAGUAGAGACCAGGUUUCAUCAUGUUGGGCAGGAUGGUCUUGAACCCCUGACCUCAGAUGAUCUGCCCAUCUCGGCCUCUCAAAGUGCUGGGAUUACAAGUGUGAGCCAUCGCGCCCGGCCUGCAAACUUUUUUGUAGGUAUUUCUGGUAAACAAAUCCUUAGGUUAUCUUUGCUGUGGUUGUGGUUUGGCUUUAGUCAUGAUUUCAAAGUAGAAAUAGCUAGGCAUUAUUUUUUGAAAUAUAUGACCUAUAUGUAGUCAAGAAUCCACUGAACAGAGGCAAGCAAACCUUUUGGAAACUGGCUUUUGGGCAGACAGUAAACGUCCAGUUUGAUGCUGGAAGCAUGAACAGCUUCAUCAGGUAGGUACUCCUCAACUCUGAUGAGUUUGUCCUUUCAGCCUAAGGGGGUGGAAGGGAGUUGUUUGAGAAUAGCAAAUACGCAUGUUGAUUGCGAGUGUGUGGAGACAAAGGCAGUUCCCACCACAGUUAGGUCCUGGCCAUUGUUUCCUCGCCUGCGAUGCUCCUUGUACAUCCUCACCCUCCUCUCCCGCCUCUGCCUUCUGCUGGGUCAAAGGUGGCCUUUUCUCUCCAGCCUUGAAUUGUUCCCUGUUGGCUUCCCAAGGGCCCAUCUGCUGGUACAGUCCACACUUCCACAGCCAAGACCCGAGAGGGCUUUCACUGCCCCAAGCCUCUCUCCUGUGACCCUGGGAUUCUGUCUUGGCAGAAUCCUUUGUCAGCGGCUCUUACUCUGUCCUUCCUGUUUGGCCACAGCUCUUUCAAUCAAUGGGUAUUCUAGAACCGCAGGAUGUCAGAGCUGGAAGGGACGCGAUACCGGUUUACACAAGGGGAAACUCCUCGAGGCUCUGGGAGGGACGGAGGGUUUUGGUGACAGAGCGAGAGCUAAAAUUGAGGAUUCCUGAAUCCAGAUCUUGCCUCCCAUCAGCCAUCUUUCUCCCAAUAAAUUUUUGUUUUGUGCAAGGCUA